GUGCCGUAGCUCGCUCGUCUCCGCCGGGGACGUGCUGCAGCAACGGCUGCAGGGCCGCUAGGCCGACUGGCGCCAGACGCGGCGCGUGGCCACGUUGGUGGUGACCUUCCACGCCAACUUCAACUACGUGUGGCUGGGCCUGCUGGAGCGCGCGCUCCCGGGCCGAGCGCCGCGCGCCAUGCUGGCCAAGUUGCUGUGCGACCAGGUGGUCGGUGCGCCCAUCGCGGUCUCGGCCUUCUACGCCGGUAUGAGCAUUCUCCAGGGAAAGGAUGACAUAUUUUUGGACCUGAAACAGAAAUUCUGGAACACCUAUAUGCAAACUCAGUCGUGGCUUUGGAGAUCACUUUAAGCUUGUCUCCAGCUGGCACACUAAGGAGGGUAAUGGAGAAGCUCCCCCACCCCCAACCCCACCCCUUCCUUCCGGAAGCAAAUCUAAGUCCAGCCCCGGCUCCAGAUCCCUCCCACAGUGGACCUAGGAAACCCUCAGCUCAGAGAACAACCCUGCAUUCCCCACACAACACCCACAAUCAGCCACUGCGGGCGAGGAGGGCACGAGGCCAGGUUCCCAAGAGCUCAGGUGAGUGACACAGUGGAACGGCCCAGGGCGCCCUCACCCUGCUCAGCUUGUGGCUCUAACAUUCCAGAAGCUGAGGCCUCUGGCAUCCCUGCCCUUUCCCCAUGGAUAUCCCAUUUCAGACAACCCUGGCCUGCGUGAAUCCCCCUCCCUUCCCUUGUUUGUUUGUUUUUUUCCCCGGGGAGGCCAGGUCUUGCUGUCACCCAGGCUGGAGUGCUGUGGGAUCCUGGCCACUGCAGCCUUGAAUUCCUGGGCUCAAGUGAUUCUCUUGCCUCAGCCUCUGGAGUAGCUAGGACUACAGGCCCUCAUCAUCCUGCCUGGUUAAUGUUUAAGAAUUUUUUUAAAGAUUUUUAGAGAUGGGGUCUUGCAAUGCUGCACCAGGUUGGUCUCCAACUCCUGGCCUCAGCCUCCCUAGGGUCUGGGAUUAUAGGUGGGAGCCACCCUGCCUAGGCCUGUGCUUUUGCUGAGUCAUCAGAGUUUUGUUCAUUCCCACAGCAGCUCUGGCCCCUAGUAGCAGCUCAGUUCCUCAAUGGGCCGUGUUUGUCCUGGAGCCCAGAUGGACUGUGGCCAGGCAAGUGGAUCACAGGCCUGGCUGGCCUGGGCGGUUUCCACAUGUGAGGGGCUGAGGGGCUCAAGGAGGGGAGCAUCUCCACUGGGUGGAGGCUGGGGGUCCCAGCAGGAAGUGGUGAGACAAAGGGCGCUGGCUGGCAGGGAGACAGCACAGGAAGGUCCUAGAGCUUCCUCAGUGCAGCUGGACUCUCCUGGAGACCUUCACACACCCUGACAUCUGGGCCUUGCCCGACGAGGGUGCUUUCACUGGUCUGCACCAUGGCCCAGGCCCUGGGAUUUUGAACAGCUCCGCAGGUGAAUGAAAGGAACAUGGAGCUGAUCCAGGACACCUCCCGCCCGCCACUGGAGUACGUGAAGGGGGUCCCGCUCAUCAAGUACUUUGCAGAGGCACUGGGGCCCCUGCAGAGCUUCCAGGCCCGGCCUGAUGACCUGCUCAUCAGCACCUACCCCAAGUCCGGCACUACCUGGGUAAGCCAGAUUCUGGACAUGAUCUACCAGGGUGGUGACCUGGAGAAGUGUCACCGAGCUCCCAUCUUCAUGCGGGUGCCCUUCCUUGAGUUCAAAGCCCCAGGGAUUCCCUCAGGGAUGGAGACUCUGAAAGACACACCGGCCCCACGACUCCUGAAGACACACCUGCCCCUGGCUCUGCUCCCCCAGACUCUGUUGGAUCAGAAGGUCAAGGUGGUCUAUGUUGCCCGCAACGCAAAGGAUGUGGCAGUUUCCUACUACCACUUCUACCACAUGGCCAAGGUGCACCCUGAGCCUGGGACCUGGGACAGCUUCCUGGAGAAGUUCAUGGUCGGAGAAGUGUCCUACGGAUCCUGGUACCAGCACGUGCAGGAGUGGUGGGAGCUGAGCCGCACCCACCCUGUUCUCUACCUCUUCUAUGAAGACAUGAAGGAGAACCCGAAAAGGGAGAUUCAAAAGAUCCUGGAGUUUGUGGGGCGCUCCCUGCCAGAGGAGACCGUGGACUUCGUGGUUCAGCACACGUCGUUCAAGGAGAUGAAGAAGAACCCUAUGACCAACUACACCACCGUCCCCCAGGAGUUCAUGGACCACAGCAUCUCCCCCUUCAUGAGGAAAGGCAUGGCUGGGGACUGGAAGACCACCUUCACCGUGGCGCAGAAUGAGCGCUUCGAUGCGGACUAUGCGGAGAAGAUGGCAGGCUGCAGCCUCAGCUUCCGCUCUGAGCUGUGAGAGGGGCUCCUGGAGUCACUGCAGAGGGAGUGUGCGAAUCAAACCUGACCAAGCGGCUCAAGAAUAAAAUAUGAAUUGAGGGCCCGGGACGGUAGGUCAUGUCUGUAAUCCCAGCAAUUUGGAGGCUGAGGUGGGAGGAUCAUUUGAGCCCAGGAGUUCGAGACCAACCUGGGCAACAUAGUGAGAUUCUGUUAAAAAAAUAAAAUAAAAUAAAACCAAUUUUUAAAAAGAGAAUAAAAUAUGAUUGUGGGCCAGGCAGAGUGGCUCAUGCCUGUAAUCCCAGCAAUUUGAGAAGUUGAGGCUAGAGGAUCACUGGAGGACAGGAGUUUGGGACCAGCCUGUUCAACAUUACAAGACAUCAUCCCUACAAAAAUUUGAGAAAAUUAUCUGUACGUGAUGGUGGGCACCUGUAGUCCCAGCUACUUGACAAGUGAAGGCAGGAGGAUCGCCUGAGCCAGGGAGGUUAUGGCUGCAGUGGGCUGACUGGGCUAAUCCACUCAAGCCUGAGGGACAGAGCAAAUCUUGCUUGAGAAAUAAAUAAAAUACAAUUUACUUAACAUAAA